ACAUUUCAGGGACACCAUGAAGGGUGGCUUCACUGGGGGUGAUGAGUACCAGAAGCACUUCCUGCCCAGGGACUACUUGGCUACUUACUACAGCUUCGAUGGCAGCCCCUCACCCGAGGCCGAGAUGCUGAAGUUUAACUUGGAAUGUCUCCACAAGACCUUCGGCCCUGGAGGCCUCCAAGGGGACACGCUGAUUGACAUUGGCUCAGGUCCUACCAUCUACCAAGUUCUUGCUGCCUGUGAUUCCUUCCAAGACAUCACUCUCUCCGACUUUACCGACCGCAACCGGGAGGAGCUGGAAAAGUGGCUGAAGAAGGAGCCGGGGGCCUAUGACUGGACCCCAGCGGUGAAAUUCGCCUGUGAGCUGGAAGGAAACAGCGGCCGAUGGGAGGAGAAGGAGGAGAAGCUGCGGGCAGCGGUGAAGCGGGUGCUCAAGUGCGAUGUCCACCUGGGCAACCCGCUGGCCCCGGCUGUGUUGCCUCUCGCCGACUGUGUGCUCACCCUGCUGGCCAUGGAGUGUGCCUGCUGUAGCCUUGAUGCCUACCGCGCUGCCCUGUGCAACCUUGCCUCACUGCUCAAGCCGGGUGGCCACCUGGUGACCACUGUCACGCUUCGGCUCCCGUCCUACAUGGUGGGGAAGCGUGAAUUUUCCUGCGUGGCCCUGGAGAAAGAGGAGGUGGAGCAGGCUGUCCUGGAUGCUGGCUUUGACAUUGAACAGCUCCUACACAGUCCCCAGAGCUACUCUGUCACCAAUGCUGCCAACAAUGGGGUCUGCUUCAUUGUGGCUCGCAAGAAGCCUGGGCCCUGAGCCAGGAGGGCCAGCCAGAGGUCUGGUCAGGCUGUGAGGCCUUGGCCAUCUGUAUGCUAGAGAGGGGUGAGGAAUGGAUACUGUCUAACAGUCUCUGAUUUCAACACUAACAUUCCAUCUUCUGAAAUUCUGAGAUUCUAACAUCCUUGUUUUAGAAUUCUAAGUUUCCAACAUUCCUCAUUCUAGGAUCCUAGGAGUGGAAUUUUCCAUUUUCUAAUAUACUAAGCCUUACAGCUAUCUUAGAUGCGAUCUGACUCCUGUGUGACUGUGGAGCACCCAGGGACGUGGUUUUAGAGUCUACCUAAUAUGUUAAGGACAAGGAAACCUCUGAGUCUACCUAAUAUGUUAAGGACAAGGAAACCUCUGGACAGUGGUAUAUUGGGGAAUUUUUUUUUUUUUUUUGAGACGGAGUCUGGCUCUGUCACCCAGGCUAGAGUGCAAUGGCACGAUCUCGGCUCACUGCAAGCUCUGCGUCCUGGGUUGACGCCAUUCUCCUGCCUCAGCCUCCCGAGUAGCUGGGACUACAGGAGCUCGCCACCACACCCAGCUAAUUUUUUUUUUUUUUUUUUUAUUUGAGACGGAGUUUCGCUCUGUCGCCCAGGCUGGAGUGCAGUGGCGCGAUCUCGACUCACUGCAAGCUCCGCCUCCCGGGUUCACGCCAUUCUCCUGCCUCAGCCUCCCGUGUAGCUGGGACUACAGGCACGCGCCACCAUGCCCGGCUAAUUUUUGUAUUUUUAGUAGAGAUGGGGUUUCACCGUGUUAGCCAGGAUGGUCUCGAUCUCCUGACCUGGUGAUCCACCCACCUUGGCCUCCCAAAGUGCUGGGAUUACAGGCGUGAGCCACCGCACCCAGCCAGGGGGAAUGUUCUAUAACCAGCUCUGUAAAGGAAAAGCACUGAUGUGUGGUAGUCACCAAUUUCUGUGGUGUAAAUACUCCCACCAUGGUUGAUUUCAAGCCACCAGUGGUUUAAUAACCAGCUCAUAAAUCUCCUAAAUAUUUUACAGUUGACUCUCAUGAGCUGAUUGGAGUCAGCUGGAACAUACCACUGCCUCUAGACUAAGGUCAGCAGAUUUAGCAAAUACAGACUGCCCCAGUUCAUUGAAUUUUAGAUAAAUGAAAUAAAUCUAUAAGGUUAAGUAUGUCCCCAGAACUGCAUGGAACAUGCUUAAUCUAAACAAUGAUUUGUUGUUCACCUGAAAUUCAAAUUUAGCUGGGUGUCCUGUAUUUCAUCUGGCAACCCUACUUCAGACCCAGGUGUAAGGUACAUGGAUGUGCUUUGGUCAAGGAAUAGGCCAAGGCAGAGAUCCAUGCCUGCAUGACUCAGUGGGUUUGGUGCACAGGCACACACCUCCACUUGUUAUAUAACCUGUUUGUGUAAGUUCAUACUUGGUCUGAGCCACUGUUGUCUGUAAAAGGUAAUUGUCCUGCUAAUGCUGUACAGGGGCUCUUGGGGUUCGGCUCAGCUCAACAUGGCUUGACAUGGUGGGCACACUGGCGCCCAGUAAGAGAGAGAGAGAGCCAAAGCUGUCCGUUUUGCAGAUGGACAGGAAGGAGCCAGGACACAGCUCAGCUUGCUCACGCCCAGAGAGAGAAAAAGUUAAGCUGCUGACCCUGAAGGCAAGGGAGAGCAGGCUGCACAGCUGUGUGUGGAAGCCACGGGCUCAAGCAGCCAAGGCAGGGCGGACAGUGUGAGAGAGCUAGUGUAAGCUGUUGAUGAGAGCUGUUGCUGAAUAAAACCAUAUUCACCUGCC